ACUCUUGUUUCGCUCCUUGACAACCCUGGCGGGGGUUCGCUGGCUGCGGCCCCGGCUCCGGCCCCCGCAGGAGCAGCACCCCCCGGGGAAAGACAUUUUCUGCUCCCACCGAGUUGGCAGGGCCUGCUUCCUGAAUCUCCUGGGUGUGUCUUAACUGCCAGUCCCAGCACCUCCUGAAAGCCCCACUCUCCUCCAGUGGUCACAGUGGAAGGAUCAUGGGAGAAACAGAAGGGAAGAAAGAUGAGGCUGAUUAUAAGCGACUGCAGACCUUCCCUCUGGUCAGGCACUCGGACAUGCCAGAGGAGAUGCGCGUGGAGACCAUGGAGCUAUGUGUCACAGCCUGUGAGAAAUUCUCCAACAACAACGAGAGCGCCGCCAAGAUGAUCAAAGAGACAAUGGACAAGAAGUUCGGCUCCUCCUGGCACGUGGUGAUCGGCGAGGGCUUUGGGUUUGAGAUCACCCACGAGGUGAAGAACCUCCUCUACCUGUACUUCGGGGGCACCCUGGCUGUGUGCGUCUGGAAGUGCUCCUGACACUCUGUCCCCUGCCCCGUCCCCUGCAGGGCCUUUUCCUGCCACUCAUCUGGGGUGGGGAGCAGCCCUAGGCAGGUCCUGGUUUUUCCAAGGAGAGUUGGGGUCUUUUCUUUUUGUCUUUGUGUACCAGUUUCCUGAGCCACGCCCAGUGUGUGAACUUGACAUCUCCAUCCCCAGGCUCUCAACCGUCUCCCUCGGAGUCUCAGGGUGUGGACGGGGCAGCGGGCAUGGGUCUGUGUGGGAGACGUGGGGUGGGGCGGUGUGACAGGGUAGAGGAGGUGGGAGAUGAGAUCUUCCGCACAGGAACACGCCAGUCCCCCUUUCUCCAGGGCUGCCUUCCCCUUGCAUCCUGGGAGCCCCACUGCCCUGCCAUCCCCAGUACUGCCGGGAAGUGUCGGCCGUCCUUGUCAUUAGUGGUCAUAUGAAAAUGGCCCCAAGAAGGAGAUGAUUCUUUCAAGGGACACAGGCAGCUUCUCUCCUUGUCCUCUGGGGAGGUGCUGACCCCUCAGAAACCCCUUCCCCCAACUUGACCCCAGGCUGAACAGACCACUGCAUCUCACUGGGCCAGCAGCCCCCCCAGCCCCCAGCCUUGGUGGGGACCAAGCAGCCUUUCCCGUCCCCUCCUCGACCCGUACAGUUGAGAGCCAGGGGCUGGUGUGUGGGAGCUGCUACCUGGCAGUUUCUCGAGGGGUCACCGAGCCUCUGGUGGGACACCUGGGCAGGAGUGCUCUCACCACGAGGCUGCUUCCGCAGGGAACCCUGGCCUGCCCGCGACUUCGCAUCAGGGACCGCAUGCUGAUUUGUACUGCUCUCUGCUGGGUUUUCUAUGUUCUUUUCGAGUGUGGGAAAAGGGUUUUAGUAGAAGGGUGAAUCGUAUUUUACACAGCGGUCUUAUUUAUAUAAAUGUCUUGGUUUUUACAAUUAAAAUGACCAAAAACUGA